CUCCCGGAAGCGGAGCACCGAGCCGGCAAAGGCUUGGGUGUGAGACAGCAGCGGUGGCAGACACCGCAGAAGCAAAGAGCAGUGAGGCUCCUGCAUUCGGGUGGAGCACCAUGGACGAAGCUGGCAGCUCUGCGAGCGGCGGGGGCUUCCGCCCGGGCGUGGACAGCCUGGACGAACCGCCCAACAGCCGCAUCUUCCUUGUGAUCAGCAAGUACACACCUGAGUCGGUGCUGAGGGAGCGCUUCUCGCCUUUUGGCGACAUCCAGGACAUCUGGGUGGUGCGGGACAAGCACACCAAGGAGUCCAAGGGCAUUGCUUUCGUCAAGUUCGCCCGCAGCUCACAGGCCUGCAGGGCCAUGGAGGAGAUGCAUGGCCAGUGCCUCGGCCCCAACGACACCAAGCCCAUCAAGGUGCGGGUGCCCGGGUCGGGGUGCCCUCGGGGGAAGGAGUGGGCCUCUUGGACCUCCCUUCACCUGCUGCUCUGCCGGGGUGAGGGAGGAGUGGAACAUCCGUUCCCGGCAGCUGACCAGACAGCACCUGGCUUGGGGACAGGGGCUGCUUUGAGGAGAGGCUCCCCUCCCACGAAGCUGCGCCGGGUUGCAGGGAAGGGGACGGGAUGCGGAGUGUUUGCCCCACGAGAGCGGACCCGGCAGCCGCGGCCACCGGGUGACAGAACAGCAGUGGCUGGGCUUCCCCUCUCCCUCGCCCUCACUAAUCCACCAGCUCUUGAGUUCACUGCCAAACUCGUCCUAGCCUACUUUGAGUACUUUUCUGACCUUCCUCUCUCAGAUGCCCAGAUUUCCAUAUAUAAAAAACGGAAAAACUCUACUUUUCCUCAGGUUUUCAUUGCUCAGUCCCGAUCAUCUGGAAGUCACCGAGAUGUUGAAGAUGAAGAACUUACAAGAAUCUUUGUUAUGAUACCAAAGUCCUACACAGAAGAAGAUCUGCGGGAAAAAUUUAAGGUGUAUGGAGAUAUCGAGUAUUGCAGCAUUAUUAAGAAUAAAGUGACUGGAGAAAGUAAAGGUUUGGGCUACGUACGAUACUUAAAACCAUCACAAGCUGCCCAAGCAAUAGAAAACUGUGAUCGAAGUUUUAGAGCAAUCUUGGCUGAACCUAAAAAUAAAGCAUCUGAAUCCUCUGAACAAGAUUAUUAUAGUAAUAUGAGGCAAGAAGCUUUGGGACAUGAACCUAGAGUAAAUAUGUUUCCAUUUGAACAACAAUCUGAAUUUUCAAGUUUUGACAAGAAUGAUAGCCGAGGCCAGGAAGCAAUCUCCAAACGCUUGUCAGUUGUAUCAAGAGUUCCUUUCACUGAAGAACAGCUUUUCAGCAUUUUUGAUAUAGUACCAGGAUUGGAAUAUUGUGAAGUUCAACGAGAUCCUUAUUCAAAUUAUGGUCAUGGAGUGGUUCAGUAUUUUAAUGUAGCAUCAGCUAUUUAUGCAAAAUACAAAUUACAUGGAUUUCAGUACCCUCCUGGGAACCGAAUAGGUGUUUCCUUCAUUGAUGAUGGAAGUAAUGCAACAGAUCUCCUUAGAAAAAUGGCAACACAGAUGGUAGCUGCACAGCUUGCAUCAAUGGUGUGGAAUAACCCAAGUCAGCAACAAUUUAUGCAAUUUGGAGGAAGCUCUGGAUCACAGUUGCCUCAAAUCCAGACAGAUGUUGUACUUCCAUCAUGCAAAAAAAAAGCUCCUGCUGAAACUCCUGUGAAAGAAAGACUUUUUAUUGUGUUUAAUCCUCAUCCUUUACCUUUAGACGUAUUAGAAGAUAUAUUCUGUCGUUUUGGUAACCUGAUCGAAGUUUACCUUGUGUCAGGAAAAAAUGUGGGGUAUGCCAAGUAUGCCGAUAGAAUAAGUGCUAAUGAUGCCAUUGCCACUCUACAUGGAAAGAUUCUGAAUGGGGUGAGACUUAAAGUUAUGCUGGCAGAUUCGCCAAGAGAAGAAUCUAACAAACGGCAAAGAACUUACUGAUUCUUGAGAAACAGUAGCUCAAGAACACAUGGAUCCUGGGAACUGAAGGUAUGGUAUUGAUAGGAGAUCAGACAGAAAUAUUCAGUUAAAAUAUCAAGUUGUAGUUCAUUCAUUACAAUGGCCAUGCUUUGACUUUAUUUAAGGUAGAAAAGUCUUGUCCUUAGUAGAAAAUGCAGCUCCCACUAUACUUUGAGAAAGUUACGAGGCCCUGUGAAAAUUUAUCUGAGUAAUUAUCAGAGAAAAAGGGAGUUCUGUGACUGUCAUAUAUGAAUUGAAGACAGUAUCUGGAUGUCAAGGUCCAUGUGAGCUAGCUAACCUAGGCUAUACCACCGUGGGACUCUUAGAAACUGCCUGUCUGACCAAAAUGCUGCAGAAGUGGCAGAAGGAAGGCAUCGGAAGACCAUUUUUAAACAGUUGUUUGUAUAUGAGGUACAAAACUCAAGAACUGUGUGAAAAGGCAAGUACCAGUACUGUUUUCUACAGAAACUGGGGGAAAUACUGAGCACAGAAGAAUAACCAAAGUGCUUCCCACCAAUAACUUCUGUGAAACUACGUUCUCUGAAUUCUUCUCCAAAUUCUUUUCUGAUUUUGUAAGUAAUGAUGUUACAACUAAUUUUUUUGCUCAUAUAUUAUUAAUAUUUUCUAGCAUUAACAAGACAUAGGUAACAGCAUUCAUUAGCUCAGAGUUUUUAAGGGUUUUGUUUGCUUGCUUGCUCUGUUUUUUUUUGUUGUUUUUUUAUGCCAGAAAAAAAAUUAAAGUCAUCUACUUUAAAGUUAUAUACUAAUUUACUAGAAGUUCUGAUAUAUAAAAAUAUGUAAUUUCAUUUUUUUCUCUCUUUGUCAACAAAGCCUAUCUGGGCCGGGCGCAGUGGCUGACGCCUGUAAUCUCAGCACUGUGGGAGGCUGAGGUGGGCGGAUCACUUGAGGUCAGGAGUUUGAGACCAGCCUGGCCAACCUGGUAAAUCCCUGUCUCUACUACAAAAAAAUUACCCAGGCAUGGUGGCAGUCACCUGUAAUCCCAGCUACUAAGGAGGCUGAGGCGAGAUAAUCUCUUGGAGUAAUCCCAGCUAUGAAGGAGGCUGACGCGGAGGUUGCAGUGAGCCAAGAUUUCGCCACUGCACUCCAGCCUGGGCGACAGAGCAAGACUCCAUCUCAAAAAUAAAUUUAAAAUAAAACAAAGCCUAUCCACUGUGUUGGGUUUUGGCCCUAGGAGAUAAUUUUUACAUUCUUAUAUCAUUGCCCCACUGGCACAAAACUCUUCCUCCCUCUUCUAUAUUAGUACAUUCGUAACUUAAUACAAGUGCCAGCGUGACCAUUUUGAAGAGGAUAGAGAAGAAGAUUUUAAUCUGUUACUUAAAGGACUGACUUUAGAAACAAUCUACAAUAGUUGCUGAGAGCACUGGACAGGGGAGCUGCUUUGGCAAUAUCAAGAUUGAGCCAACAGUGGCAAAAAAAGAGUGUACUAGGAAAGAUAGCACCUACCUUUGGUUUAUCAUCACCAACUCCUACCAGGAUUCAUCUACCAUUAGGUACCAUCUUGGCUUGUUUAUUUCACCAGAAAUUCCUAACAGGACUCAUCUCCUACUACUUUUAGCCUAAAUCUGGGAAUCAUAGGCAAUAGGGAGUCUAUACCAGGUACUGUAAUGUUGUCCCUACAGUCUUAUUUUACUAUGAUAACUCAAAGGAGGUAUUUCACACACAAAAAGAAAUCAGAAGUAAAUCUCCCUUACAUCAUCCUUAAAGAUUAGCAAUGUGCCUGGAAUAUCCAGCUUCUACUUAAUAGCUUUUAGCUAUUUGUAGCAGGAAUUUAUCAUGUCUUCUAGAUCUUGUUGAUAUUAUUAGCCUUUAGUUCCCCAAAAAUGAGUUUCAUAUGUGGUACCCACAUGGCCUUUUUGGGUCUGUUUUCUCAUCUAGAAAAUAAGAAAGAUAAUAAUUAUUAGUGUAAAUACAAGCCUCUGCAAACCCUCGUCUCUCAGGAUUCUACAGAAACAUCCUGGAAAACAUUAAGUAGGAAGAAAAUUUAUAUCAAUCAUAGAAACUUAGGUUAAGGUUAGUGGAAACUAGAAAGAAUUUCUACUAAAUAGAAAUUCAGUAGAAUCCCAGUAAGGGGUAGGAUUUUAAAAAAUGGCUGACUCCAAUUCUGCAUUGGAACAUGCUGUUAAUAAAACAAGAUGACAGCCCAGUGUGAUGGCUCACGCCUGUAAUCCCAGCACUUUGGGAGGCCGAGGUGGGCAGAUCACGAGGUCAGGAGAUCGAGACCAUCCUGGUUAACAUGGUGAAACCCCUUCUGUACUAAAAAUACAAAAAAUUAGGCAGGUGUGGUGGCGGGCGCCUGUAGUCCCAGCUACUUGGGAGGCUGAGGCAGGAGAAAGGUGUAAACCCGGGAGGCGGAACUUGCAGUGAGCCGAGAUCACGCCACUGCACUCCAGCCUGAGCGACAGAGCGAGACUCCGUCUCAAACAAACAAAAACAAAUAAAACAAGAUGACACCUUAGCCUCCCAUCUUCUGACACUCCUUAUUAACUUAUGUAUGAGAAGGCUAUACUGUUAAUUUGAGACAGCUAUUGAGAGUCUUGUCAUAAUAGGCUUCUUUCUGCAUUCCUUCACUAGUGGCCCUGAAGCUGCACUAUGUUGGAGGUUUCCUUGACUAAGAGAACCACAUGCGGCAUUCAGCUCAGUAGGGGAGUCAUAAAAGAUCUCGCCUCUGACCAGAAGAGUAUGAAUGACAAAGGUGACAUAACCAGCACAGAAAGAUGUCUUAGCCUCUGCACAUCAGCUGAUUUAGAAUACUUAUGUAGAUAGCGGUUGGGGUCGGGGGGGUGCGGAAUGUUCUUUUCAGCUUCUUUGCCCUGAGAACUUUGAUCUUAUUGCAAGGAAGUCCCUUACCCUCUUCUACCCUAGAUCUGAUGGACCUCCUGGGAUUUCCUGGGGAAAUGAAAUGAGUCUAACACCUUUGACCACCUGCUGGAUAUUAUAUCAGCACUUACUUAAGUAAGCUGUGGAAGAGCUGAAAGCAGUAUUCAGAGUCUGACAGUUCUCUGCAAUUGGCCUAGAUAAACUCAUUGUGAAAUAAGUAACUAAAUGGGCAAAAGAUUUGAACAAGCACUUCACAAAAGAAGACCAAGAAGAGGGCAGGGUUUUUUGUUUGGGGAGUUUUAUUUAGUUUUGUUUUGGGGUUGUUUUGUUUUGGCAGGGGACAGGAGUAGUGGAUAGAUUCAUUUUGUAAAGAAAUAUUAAAAUAUUCUUUUUAAUUUGAUAGUUAAUAUAAGCUUAAGAAUCUUUUAAAACUCAGAAUGUUCAGCCGUAUUAGUCAUCAAUGAACUGCUCAUUAAAACUACAAUAAGCUACCCUAACAGUGGUAUGAACAGCAAGAAUUAAAAUGUUGACAAUACCAAGUACUGGUGACAGUGUGAAGCAACAAGAACUGCUGAUGCAAAUUGGCUCAACCGCUUGGGAAAAUGUUUGACAGUAUCUACUAAAGUUGAACAUAUGUAUACCCUCGACUCAGCAAUUCCACUUCUAAGCAUAUAUCCAACAAAGAUGUGUACAUAUAUGUACCAAAAGACACAUACAAAAACAUUCUUGGUAUUAUUCAUAGUAGCCCCAAAGUGGAAACAACCCCAAUGUCCAUGAACAGAAUGCAUAUGACACUCUAUAGCAAGGAAAUGAGCUAACUUGCUACACUUAUAAUGAUUUGAAGGAAUCUCACAAACAUAAUGUUGAACAAAAGCAACCAGCCAACAAAAGAUGUGCUGUAGGAUUCCCAGUUACAGAGUUCAAAAACAAGCAAAACAUAUCUUUGAGCAGAAUGGAAUGGGGGAGUUCACAAAGGGAGUUAUGGUGUGCUGGUGGUCUUGUUUUUCUUGACCAGGAUGGGGAUAACUGAUCGUUUUUGAGCUGUACUCUAUGGAGUAUGCAUUUUUUAUUUAUCUUAUACUUCAAUUAAAGUUUUUCUUUCUUAGUGAAUAAAGCAAAAAUCAGCAUGAGGCUGGUGAAACAGACAGUUCUGCAGAAUGAGAGAAGAACAAUGUCCUGAAGCAUUUAGAAAGAAGGACUUUGUUCUUCCAGUGCUUAUAGAACAAAAAAUAUUAGAAAAUAUCUGCUUUUGCUCCCCCUAUGGUGCAGCAGGGUAUUAUGAUGGCAAGAGGGCAGGAAAAUAAGAGUGAGAAAAGAAAGGGAGAAGCUAAAUUAAUAUUUGAGUCAGAAAUAGUAAAUAGUCAUAGCACUAAAGAAAAUUGAAUCCAUGAUGAACAGUGAAUACUGAACUACUUUUCAGAAUCCUGUGGGUUCUCAUGAGUCCACAAAGCGAAGAUGGAGGGAAGUUCCCCCACUUUUUGUUCAUUAUCCAGAUCAGAACUGCUUUCAUCAAUGUUAUAUAUUGUGCUUUAAAAGCUUUCUUUUAAAGGAUUCUCUGCAGCUUAAAUAAGUUAGGAUGAACAAAAAGCACCAGAGCAAAAGAUAAAAAGCACCCUCCGACAAAUAUAGUAAGAGAAAAGGUGCAGAUCAAAAAGGCUGAUUACAGAGAUUUAUCCUUUGACUAAUAGAUGUUCCCAAUAAACAAUAACUCGUUUUAAUAGAAGAAACAUGGUUGAUCUAAAAAAUUUUAAAAGUCACAAGACUGAAGAUCCUCUUCUACACAUUUUAAAUGCCAUCUGGAAUGGAGCAAUGUCUGUAGUUUUGUAGCCCAAGAUUCCUCUACUCAUCCAAAUUGUAAAGGUAACAGGCAUUCUGUGAUAUACAAUGUACUGCUCAUUUGCCCUUUCUGGAAAAAAAUUAAUCACCACACUCCCAAAAUGAAUCAAAAUUAAGAAUAAAAGAAGAAGGAAAGAAAGGCCAGUCGGUGAGUAUUGAAAUCAUCACUGAAACUAUUAGAAUAAUGAAGGUAAUUGUAAAUUUCAUUUUUUAAAAAAAGUUUUAUUAUAUGACUUAUCUAUUCCGAAAUUUUUCAGUGGGAUUUAUAACCCUAGGUUAAGUUAAUGAAGGCCAAGAAGGAAUGGCAGUUUAUUUUUUGGGGGGGAUGGAGGUGGGUGAGGGGUAAAAUCCUUCUCUUUUGUAAAGAAAUAUUAAAAUUCAUUCUUUUUUUACUUUGAUAAUUAAAUGUAAGAUUAAGAAUCUUUUGAAGUCUGUUAAGGUGCUUAAUAAUAAAAUUAAUAACAGAA